GUACUCGCGGCGGCCCGGCCCUCGCCCGGGAGUGCGUGUGUGCGCGCGUGUGUGCGCGAGUGAGUGUGUGCGCGGGGUGCGCGCGCGGGCGGGAGUGGGCGCGCGCGGGGAAAGGCCCGAAAACACCUUAGUUUGCACCGAGAGACCAUUUGCAGCGGAACCCGAAAGUUUGUAAGAGGAAGAGAGCGCGCGGCGAGCGAGCGAGCGGGCCGGGGGCAGCGGCAGCGGCGCCGGGGACCAUGGUGCUGCCGGCGCCUCCUCCGCGGGCGUGAAGGCGGCGCUCCUACUCCCUCCCCGGACUCCGCGGUGUCCCAGAAGCUUUUGUUGACAAUUCCAGUUUCCGAACAAAACAUUUCGGCAAUGGUGAGGGCUUCGAUCCCUUCUCUGAUUUGCUGUCAGCCAUGAACGGAUGGAUGUGAUGCCUGCUAGCCAAAAGGCUUCCCUCUGUGUGUUGCAGUCCUGUGGCAUUAUGCAUGCCCCCUCCCAGUGACCCCAGGCUUUUUAUGGCUGUGAGACACGUUAAAAUUUCAGGGGUAAGACGUGACCUUUUGAGGUGACUAUAACUGAAGAUUGCUUUACAGAAGCCAAAAAAGGUUUUUGAGUCAUGAUGCAAGAAUCUGGGACUGAGACAAAAAGUAACGGUUCAGCCAUCCAGAAUGGGUCGGGCGGCAGCAACCACUUACUAGAGUGCGGCGGUCUUCGGGAGGGGCGGUCCAACGGAGAGACGCCGGCCGUGGACAUCGGGGCAGCUGACCUCGCCCACGCCCAGCAGCAGCAGCAACAGGCACUUCAGGUGGCAAGACAGCUCCUUCUUCAGCAGCAACAGCAGCAGCAAGUUAGUGGAUUAAAAUCUCCCAAGAGGAAUGACAAACAACCAGCUCUUCAGGUUCCCGUGUCAGUGGCUAUGAUGACACCUCAAGUUAUCACUCCCCAGCAAAUGCAGCAGAUCCUCCAGCAACAAGUGCUGAGCCCUCAGCAGCUCCAGGUUCUCCUCCAGCAGCAGCAGGCCCUCAUGCUUCAACAGCAGCAGCUUCAAGAGUUUUAUAAAAAACAACAGGAACAGUUGCAGCUUCAACUUUUACAACAACAACAUGCUGGAAAACAGCCUAAAGAGCAACAGCAGGUGGCUACCCAGCAGUUGGCUUUUCAGCAGCAGCUUUUACAGAUGCAGCAGUUACAGCAGCAGCACCUCCUGUCUUUGCAGCGCCAAGGCCUUCUGACAAUUCAGCCCGGGCAGCCUGCCCUUCCCCUUCAACCUCUUGCUCAAGGCAUGAUUCCAACAGAACUGCAGCAGCUCUGGAAAGAAGUGACAAGUGCUCAUACUGCAGAAGAAACCACAGGCAACAAUCACAGCAGUUUGGAUCUGACCACGACAUGUGUCUCCUCCUCUGCACCUUCCAAGACCUCCUUAAUAAUGAACCCACAUGCCUCUACCAAUGGACAGCUCUCAGUCCACACUCCCAAAAGGGAAAGUUUGUCCCAUGAGGAGCACCCCCAUAGCCAUCCUCUCUAUGGACAUGGUGUAUGCAAGUGGCCAGGCUGUGAAGCAGUGUGCGAAGAUUUCCAAUCAUUUCUAAAACAUCUCAACAGUGAGCAUGCGCUGGACGAUAGAAGUACAGCCCAAUGUAGAGUACAAAUGCAGGUUGUACAGCAGUUAGAGCUACAGCUUGCAAAAGACAAAGAACGCCUGCAAGCCAUGAUGACCCACCUGCAUGUGAAGUCUACAGAACCCAAAGCCGCCCCUCAGCCCUUGAAUCUGGUAUCAAGUGUCACUCUCUCCAAGUCCGCAUCGGAGGCUUCUCCACAGAGCUUACCUCAUACUCCAACGACCCCAACCGCCCCCCUGACUCCCGUCACCCAAGGCCCCUCUGUCAUCACAACCACCAGCAUGCACACGGUGGGACCCAUCCGCAGGCGGUACUCAGACAAAUACAACGUGCCCAUUUCGUCAGCAGAUAUUGCGCAGAACCAAGAAUUUUAUAAGAACGCAGAAGUUAGACCACCAUUUACAUAUGCAUCUUUAAUUAGGCAGGCCAUUCUCGAAUCUCCAGAAAAGCAGCUAACACUAAAUGAGAUCUAUAACUGGUUCACACGAAUGUUUGCUUACUUCCGACGCAACGCGGCCACGUGGAAGAAUGCAGUGCGUCAUAAUCUUAGUCUUCACAAGUGUUUUGUGCGAGUAGAAAACGUUAAAGGGGCAGUAUGGACAGUGGAUGAAGUAGAAUUCCAAAAACGAAGGCCACAAAAGAUCAGUGGUAACCCUUCCCUUAUUAAAAACAUGCAGAGCAGCCACGCCUACUGCACACCUCUCAAUGCAGCUUUACAGGCUUCAAUGGCUGAGAAUAGUAUACCUCUAUACACUACCGCUUCCAUGGGAAAUCCCACUCUGGGCAACUUAGCCAGCGCAAUACGGGAAGAGCUGAACGGGGCAAUGGAGCAUACCAACAGCAACGAGAGUGACAGCAGUCCAGGCAGAUCUCCUAUGCAAGCCGUGCAUCCUGUACACGUCAAAGAAGAGCCCCUCGAUCCAGAGGAAGCUGAAGGGCCCCUGUCCUUAGUGACAACAGCCAACCACAGUCCAGAUUUUGACCAUGACAGAGAUUACGAAGAUGAACCAGUAAACGAGGACAUGGAGUGACUAUCGGGGCGGGCCAACCCCGAGAAUGAAGAUUGGAAAAAGGAAAAAAAAAAAAACACGUCAAAAGUUAGCAGUGAAAUUGUUCUCCAUUUGUUGUACAGUCUGGAGGAUUUUCACUACGUUUUGACAACUCUGAAAUGUGUUAACUCUUAGUGCCAUCAAGAACCCCAUUUGGGAGUAUUUUUGAUUUUUCUACUUUUUGUUGAAAAAAGGAAUUUGUACUCUGUGCAUUGGAUGGACUUGUUUGGUACUUGGGAUUUUCCUCUCUUAACCGUCAACAUCAGUGUUGUAAAUUUGCUAAACUGAUUCACUUUUAGCAGCAGACUUUGAACUGCAGUCCUGCCAACGUUGGACACUGAGGACGCCCGACAGAGCUUGUGCACCUAAGCUGCAGACCAAGCCUUUGCCCAGAAUUUAAGGAUUCCAAUGGACGACCUAUUUGCACAGUACUGCAUGUUGAUUAUCACUGCCUUUACUCCUUUUUUUUUUUUUUUUUUUUUUUUUUUUUUGCUUCCAGUUGGGAUGGGGAAGGCCUUUGUGUGUGUAUUGGGGGGAGGGGUUAAAAAAUAAUUAUCCCAAACUUUUUAAUGUAUUGCUUUUUUUUUUUUUUUUUUUCCUUCUACUAUACCAUUUUAAGUUCUGACCUCAGGCCUCCAUUUGGGCCGAUGGCCUCUUGGAGGCUUAAAGUUUUCUGUACCUUGUGAUGAAUGUUAAUAGGUGUUUUUAUUAUACAAAGCUGAAUGUCAUUUCUCGUUUGUAGCUUUCUGUCACUCAUUCCAUCUUCCUUCAGACAUCACCACGUUUCUCUAAAGUCAGAAAACAUUCCGUUUUGGUCUUUUUCAAAAAGGUCCCAAAUGCUGCACUCUACACAUGAAGGCCCUCUCACACAGACGUGACGUCCUGCCAGAAAGAGAAUGAAUGACAGAAAAAAAAAAGAGAGACAAACUCUAGGAACAAUGCCGAUUCAUUCCACGCAGCAGUAUUGGGGGUGGUUCGGGGGAGGGGUGUUUCGGAUUUUCUUUUUUUCUUUUCUUUUCUUUUUUUUUUUUUGCAGCAACCAUUAAUAAAUGCCACCACAUUCUACCAGCACAAGGAAACAUAGGCAGCACUGAAAAAAAAAAAAAAGCUCAUAUUAAUUAGACUGACAAUAUGGCCUUGGAAGGCUCUCCCUUGUGGAACCAAGUUGCCAUGGGCCUUGGGUGCUCUGCGAUAACGGGUGUGGGUUGGUUUUGUUUGCAAAAUGGCCAAAAAAAAAAACCGGCUUCCCCGAGCAGCUGCCCUGAAAGUAGGGGUGGCGGCGGCGGCGCUGAGUUUAUACAUUAGUUCAGACCUACUUGGUGGCAUUAAACUGUUUGAAUGCAAAUUCGAUUUCAGAUUGAACUUGUUAAGGGAGUUAACGAGGGCUGAGUUCAGCAAAUGCUAAAGUGUUAAUUUCAAAUAUGCAAAUUUGGUACUGCAGUUUGUUAUGCAAUAUUAUAUCACCAACCCAGUAUCACAAAAACUCAUAGAAGAUAUCAUGUAGGCCCUGGGCUUUGGGGGGGUCCCAAACAUGGUAUGCAGAAAUGUGAUGGUUACAGGUCAGUACAACCUCAGUCCUUAGAACCCCUCCACACUUCAGCUCUGCACCCACUUUCCUGUCAUUUAUUUAUAUAGGACUGUAGUUUUUUUUAGUUCGAGAGCCUUUCGAAGCUUAAUUUAUAUUCUUUCUUUGUACCUUUUUUCUAAAAUUACCAAAGAUAUUACACAAAGGUAAAUUAUGUUCUCUGUUUUAUGCUUUAUCUGAUGAAGCCAAAUAUCCUCUUAUUGUUGAUCAAAGGAGGCAAAAGAAUUUAGAGGCAAAUGACAAGCGAUAGGCUAUUGCAACCUGAGAAAGAGAACUGCUCCUUCAUCGUAAAUUUAGAAGACCAAGUAGAUAAUGGAACCAAAGUUGUUACUUUUUUCUAGUAGUUAUUUUUCCUUUUUCUUUUUGUGUACCUCUACAGAGACCAAAACUCAUUCUCUUAAAGAGAUUUUAUGGGGCUACUGCAGAUAAAAAUAGGACACAAUAUUAAAGGAGCUACAGAAGGAAGGGAGUCCCAUCUCAAAAAAAAAAUGAAUGUAUGCCACUGCAAUUAGAGUAUCCAAUAAAGGAGACAGUUUAGAGUCAGGACAGAAAAGCUUCCAUAAUUGAACUAGAUUACAUAAUAGUAUUUCUAGAAAAAGAGAUAUUUUUAGAUUGUAUGCCACUUUUGUUUAAGAACUGUGCUGUGAUCACUGUAUUAAUUUUGGUUUAUCUUGGCAUAUAUCCUUCAGUUUGUUUUUAUUUUUAAUUUUUCCUUUUUUUCCGAUUAGGCUUUGGUCAGCAUUUUUCAUUUAAAGAAAAGUAACACUCCCAUCCACUCAUAAGCUUGGUACAAAAACUUCUCUGGCAGUUACUUUUGAAGCUUCACUCUGCUUUCUGUAUAAAGGGCAGUCUGUGGUCACGCAAGACUUUAAAAAAAAAAAAAAAAAAAAAAAAAAAAAAAAAAAAAAAAACUUUUCCAGGCAGCUUCAUGAUGUGCAGGCAGUAGCCAGACAGGGUCAUGGGAAGGGGGCCCUGUGCUUCUAAACUGAGUGGUUGCUGGUUAGUUUGGUAUUCAAAAGAGGAUAAAAAUCUGGUAGAUUAGUUCAUUCUCAGCAUGUGUAGCUAGACAUGAGUAAAGAUAACAGCAUGAGAAACUGUUAGUACGCAUACCUCAGUUCAAACCUUUAGGGAAUGAUUAAAAUUUAAAAAAAAAACAUUUCACUCAGUUGCACUUAGUCGUAUGUCUUGCAUGCUUAGUCUAAAGACUGUAGCAAAAAAAAAAAAAAAAGAAAAAUUAGAUUUUACAUAUCUUUGCAGGUAUCACAGCCUUGCAGAAGAACCAACUGAAAAAAAAAUUCUCAGGCUUUACAGCAAGCAAACUUCACUAUGAUUUUUACAAUUCUGAUUCUGUAUCCCCUGGGGGUUAUCCCAGUUGCUUCUUUAGGAUGGGGUUUAUUACGUUGUACAUAUAUCCCGAUGUGUCUGUGUGAAUCUUUGUCUUUUUUGGGGGAGGGCAGAGGGCGGUUCUUUUUUUAGAUAUUGUUCCUAAAAAGGAAUAAAUGCAUACACCUGUUUGUCAAAACACCUUUGCUUUUUGUGCAACUGCUUUAUAUUAACGAUACUAAAAAAAAAUAGCUUUGGAAAAAAAACUACUGUAUGUAACGGAAUUGCAGAAUAUGCUGCACAUGUAUUUUAUUUAGUUAUCCUUGCUUUAAGAAUAUUGGAUGACAUUUCCUGACAUGUGGGAGGGAGAAACUCCCUAACUUUUUUUUUCUGCUUUUAAACUGUAACAUAGUUGAAGAUUUCUUUUUUCUGUUCUCAUUGAUUGGAGCAUUUUGUACAGGUUUUGUGUGUGUGUGUGUGUGUGUGUGCGCGCGUGCGUGUGUGUUAAUCUGUUUUUUGAUACAUUCCUAUCCCUUGUGUUUAUCCUACCACUGCCUUCCUGGCUAUCUUAAACAAGUUCAUACAUUUGAAAAGAAAAAAAAAUGUUGUUUAAAAAAUGUUUUCUCCUGCUGCAGUAAAUAUUUUGCAUGAUGAAAUUCCAGGGUCACACUUUUCCAAGUUUAUCAGUGAAGUAGUGAUUAACAAUGGGGAGUGUCAAAACUAUUGAACUUUUGUAUAAAAAAAAAAAAACUUUACAAGGUGCCAAGAUGUAAAGAAAAUCUGUUACUUUUUUUUUCUCAAAGAAAAGCAUACAUUAGGGAGGUAGUCCCGUGUGUCAGACAAAUGCACUGUCAGGAAUGAGGAUCCAACCUACCUGUCCCUAGAGUCCGUCUUGUAAGAUGAGUUAGGCUGCCCCUUGGACCAGCCACAAAAUGGAAUAUCAAGGCUUAUGUACAUACGUGAAGAGUUACCACCAGUCCUGCCACCUUUGGACAGCUCUAACACCAUCCCCAGCAUCCAGUCAGACCUAGUAAAGAAAACCUUGGAUUCUUAACCCAAGAUAGGCUGUAAAUCACUAGCUUUUUUUUCCUCAUGAAAAAAAAUAGAGUUAAAAAAUAUUUCCUCUCUUUUCCAUAUUCCAGCUGAACUCCGUUUCCAAAGGCACAAAGAAGAGUGUGCUUAUUCAGAUUUUGAAUCUUUUUGGUACCUUUUGGUUAAUGACAUAGCCUCCUGAAAUUCUGGAUGUCUUCAAAGUCAGUUUUGCUUCUUUAUCCUGAAAAUCAGAUUUACAAUGCUGAAGGCAUUUCUUGGGCCCAGUGUAGCUCACGCAAUCUCUGCUACCCAUAAGCCUUGAUGAAGAUGAUACAGUCCGGACUGUGAGCAUGGUGCUUCAUGUAUAUGUGCUGCCAGUAACAAGAAUUUUUUUGUUUUGUUUUGUUUUGUUUUGAUAAGGCAUAAAAGAAACUCAUUCCUUGACAUCAACUGUAAUUCCAUCAUUCCAUGUCUGCGGAUACAGACAAUAAAAAAAAUGUUGUGUAGUCAGUACUAAUUACUGACAUUAUAAGCAUUCUCAAAUGCAAUAAAAAUGCUGGUUGUUCACGCUGGUAGUAAAA